GAACCCCACCCGCACUCCAAUGAGGUCACAAUGGCUGGAGCUCUGAGGGGCCCAGGCUCCCUGAGCCAGGAGGAGAGGAGAAAGUCCAAGGAAAGAUGGCUGGCAGUCACCCCUACUUCAACCUGCCUGACUCCACACACCCAUCGCCGCCCUCCGCUCCACCCAGCCUCCGCUGGCACCAGCGCUGCCAGCCCUCUGGUGCCACCAAUGGCCUGCUGGUGGCCCUGCUGGGUGGGGGCCUGCCUGCUGGCUUCGUGGGCCCCCUUUCUCGUAUGGCUUACCAGGGUUCCAACCUGCCCUCGCUGGAGCUGCUCAUCUGUCGAUGCCUCUUCCACCUCCCUAUUGCCCUGCUACUUAAACUGCGUGGCGACCCCCUUCUGGGACCUCCUGACAUCCGAGGCUGGGCCUGCUUCUGUGCCCUGCUCAACGUCCUCAGCAUUGGAUGUGCCUACAGUGCAGUUCAGGUGGUGCCCGCUGGCAACGCUGCCACUGUUCGCAAAGGUUCUUCCACCGUAUGCUCCGCUGUCCUCACCCUCUGCCUUGAGAGCCAGGGUCUCGGUGGCUACGAGUGGUGUGGACUGUUGGGCAGCAUCCUAGGACUAAUCAUCAUUCUGGGACCUGGACUCUGGACACUACAGGAGGGGACCACAGGUGUCUACACCACCCUGGGCUAUGUGCAGGCUUUCCUGGGAGGCCUGGCGCUGUCCCUGGGGCUUCUGGUCUAUCGUUCUCUGCACUUUCCCUCCUGCCUCCCAACAGUGGCCUUCCUAUCUGGCUUGGUGGGGCUGCUGGGCUGUGUGCCAGGCCUCUUUGUGCUGCAGACCCCCGUGUUGCCCAGUGACCUCCUGAGUUGGAGUUGUGUGGGGGCAGAGGGGAUCCUCGCCUUGGUCUCCUUCACAUGUGUGGGCUAUGCGGUCACCAAGGCCCACCCUGCCCUGGUGUGCGCUGUCCUGCAUUCCGAGGUGGUUGUGGCCCUUAUACUGCAGUAUUAUAUGCUCCAUGAGACUGUGGCACUUUCUGACAUCAUGGGGGCAGGGGUUGUGCUGGGCAGCAUUGCCAUCAUUACAGCCCGGAACCUCAGCUGUGAGAGGACAGGGAAGGUGGAGGAGUGAGAUAGAACUUGGGAGCCCGGGGGUUGGGAGGGACAGGGAUAAAUAAAGACAAAGACUGAAGACAAAAAAAAAAUAAAAGAAAAAAAAUAAUUAUAAUAAAUCCUAGGAAAGAGUGAAAGUCUAACUUCCAUAGCACAUUAUAAUAUUGAGAUGUUCAGUUAUAAUAAAAAUAUCACAAAGCAUGCAAACAAAUGAGAAAUCUGGCUUAUUUACAGGAAUAAAAUUAAUUGAACUAUC